GCGCCACUACUGGCGCAUGAGAUGCGCUCAAGCAGAGGGUACUCCACCAGCGAGGAUACACCGAGCCGACGGGGAUCUCGGUCUCGGCGCCGGAAGCCUCUGAGAGCCGAAUCUGGAACCGGAUGUGGCUGCUUCCUGCCCCGCCCCCUGCCGAGGGGGCGGGAAUCGAGGGCCCUUCGGAAAACCCGGCCGGGAUUUCGGGGCUGGAGACUGGAAUCUUUAUUCCAGUUCAUUGCGGGUCGACGUGGUCUCCAGAAUCCCCGAGUGUAGAGGCGGAGGACAGUGGAGCUGGGGACUCGGGCGCCUGGGUCCUGGUCCCUGAGCGUCCAGCGCUCCCCUAGUCCGCGGCCCUGGCUCCUGUCCUCACUUCCUUCCCCUUUUGGCUCCUGCUCUCGGAGCGGGCGGACGCGGGGGGGAGCGGAAAGGGCGGGAGGGCCCAGGAGCCCGGCGGGGGGGUUCAAGGGGGUACGGAAAAGCCGGGGAGGGGACUCGGUCCGGGGCCGGAGACCGACGGCAACAGCGGCUCAGGACCCACGCUGCCCCCACCCCUCCCGAGCAGGCGCCCCCAUGGCCCGACCCCGCUGAUUCCUUCACUCGGCCAUGCUCCCGCGGCCCCUGCGGCUGCUUUUGGACACGAGCCCCCCCGGGGGAGUCGUACUGAGCAGCUUCCGAAGCCGGGACCCCGAAGAGGGUGGGGGCCCAGGUGGCCUGGUCGUGGGCGGGGGGCAGGAGGAAGAGGAGGAGGAAGAAGAAGAGGCCCCUGUGUCCGUCUGGGAUGAGGAGGAGGAUGGUGCCGUGUUUACCGUCACAAGCCGCCAAUAUCGACCUCUUGAUCCCUUGGUCCCUAUGCCUCCCCCACGUUCCUCCCGACGGCUCCGAGCUGGCACUCUGGAGGCCCUGGUCAGACACCUACUGGAUACCCGGACAUCAGGGACUGAUGUGAGCUUCAUGUCAGCCUUCCUGGCUACCCACCGGGCCUUCACCUCCACGCCUGCCUUGCUAGGGCUUAUGGCUGACAGGCUGGAAGCCCUUGAAUCUCAUCCUACCGACGAACUAGAGAGGACAACAGAGGUAGCCAUCUCUGUACUGUCAACCUGGCUGGCCUCUCACCCUGAGGAUUUUGGCUCUGAGGCCAAGGGUCAGCUUGACCGGCUUGAGAGCUUCUUACUUCAGACAGGGUAUGCAGCAGGGAAGGGUGUUGGGGGGGGCAGCGCUGACCUCAUCCGCAAUCUCCGGUCCCGGGUGGACCCCCAGGCCCCCGACCUUCCUAAGCCCCUGGCCCUCCCCGGCGAUCCCCCUGCUGACCCCACGGAUGUCCUGGUGUUCCUCGCUGACCACUUGGCCGAACAGCUGACCCUGCUAGAUGCGGAACUUUUUCUCAAUUUGAUCCCCUCUCAGUGCCUGGGAGGCCUGUGGGGUCACAGAGACCGGCCAGGACAUUCUCACCUCUGCCCAUCUGUCCGAGCUACUGUCACACAGUUUAACAAGGUGGCAGGGGCAGUGGUUAGUUCUGUCCUGGGGGCUACUUCCACUGGAGAGGGACCUGGGGAGGUGACCAUACGGCCACUCCGUCCCCCACAGAGGGCCCGGCUCCUGGAGAAGUGGAUCCGCGUGGCAGAGGAGUGCCGGCUGCUCCGAAACUUCUCUUCAGUUUAUGCCGUGGUGUCAGCCCUGCAGUCCAGCCCCAUCCACAGGCUUCGGGCAGCCUGGGGGGAAGCAACCAGGGACAGCCUCAGAGUCUUUUCCAGCCUCUGCCAGAUUUUCUCCGAGGAGGAUAAUUAUUCCCAGAGUCGGGAGCUGCUCGUGCAGGAGGUGAAGCUGCAGUCUCCUCUGGAGCCACACUCCAAGAAGGCCCCGAGGUCUGGCUCCCGGGGUGGGAAUGGAUACAUCAAUUUUGACAAGCGGAGGAAGGAGUUUGCAGUCCUUUCUGAGUUGCGACGGCUCCAGAAUGAAUGUCGUGGCUAUAACCUCCAACCUGACCAUGAUAUCCAGAGGUGGCUACAGGGGCUCCGGCCACUGACAGAGGCUCAGAGCCAUCGUGUAUCCUGUGAGGUGGAGCCACCUGGUUCCAGUGACCCUCCUGCCCCACGGGUGCUUCGGCCAACAUUGGUCAUCUCGCAGUGGACAGAGGUUUUGGGCUCUGUUGGGGUCCCUACCCCGCUUGUGUCCUGUGACCGGCCCAGUACUGGGGGAGAUGAGGCGCCUACAACUCCUGCUCCUCUGCUGACUCGGCUGGCCCAGCACAUGAAGUGGCCAUCUGUCUCGUCACUAGACUCUGCCUUGGAAAGCAGUCCAUCCCUGCACAGUCCAGCUGACCCCAGCCACCUCUCCCCACCAGCCUCCUCCCCUAGGCCUUCUCGAGGUCACCGCCGCUCAGCCUCCUGUGGCUCCCCGCUGAGUGGGGGUGCAGAAGAGGCCUCCGGGGGGACUGGAUAUGGGGGAGAGGGAUCUGGGCCAGGGGCCUCUGAUUGCCGUAUCAUCCGAGUCCAGAUGGAGUUGGGGGAAGAUGGCAGUGUCUAUAAGAGCAUUUUGGUGACAAGCCAGGACAAGGCUCCAAGUGUCAUCAGUCGUGUCCUUAAGAAAAACAAUCGUGACUCUGCAGUGGCUUCAGAGUAUGAGCUGGUACAGCUGCUACCAGGGGAGCGAGAGCUGACUAUCCCAGCCUCGGCUAAUGUAUUCUACGCCAUGGAUGGAGCUUCACACGAUUUCCUCCUGCGGCAGCGGCGAAGGUCCUCUACUGCUACACCUGGCGUCACCAGUGGCCCGUCUGCCUCAGGAACUCCUCCGAGUGAGGGAGGAGGGGGCUCCUUUCCCAGGAUCAAGGCCACAGGGAGGAAGAUUGCACGGGCACUGUUCUGAGGAGGAAGCCCCGUUGGCUUACAGAAGUCAUGGUGUUCAUACCAGAUGUGGGUAGCCAUCCUGAAUGGUGGCAAUUAUAUCACAUUGAGACAGAAAUUCAGAAAGGGAGCCAGCCACCCUGGGGCAGUGAAGUGCCACUGGUUUACCAGACAGCUGAGAAAUCCAGCCCUGUGGGAACUGGUGUCUUAUAACCAAGUUGGAUACCUGUGUAUAGCUUCCCACCUUCCAUGAGUGCAGCACACAGGUAGUGCUGGAAAAACGCAUCAGUUUCUGAUUCUUGGCCAUAUCCUAACAUGCAAGGGCCAAGCAAAGGCUUCAAGGCUCUGAGCCCCAGGGCAGAGGGGAAUGGCAAAAUGUAGGUCCUCGCAGGAGCUCUUCUUCCCACUCUGGGGGUUUCUAUCACUGUGACAACACUAAGAUAAUAAACCAAAACACUACCUGAAUUCUA